GCUCGCGCGCGCGCGCACGGCCGGCCACGGCGCGCCGGGGUUGGCUGCUACAGGGACCGCGGUGGCGGCGGCGGCCUCGACAGCGGUAGUGCCUUCUACUCCGCUUUUUUAGUUUCCUCCGCCCCCUCCCGUGGGACGCUGUUGUGUGGCUGCCUUAAAAAAAAACGCAACUUUAUUGUUCCUCAGCCCCACCUCCGGCUCGGCGGGCGUCCUCAGGAUGCACUGAGGCUGAGGGGAGGGGAGGCGGCGGAGGGUCGAGGUCGCGGUCCCUCUCCUCCGAGCGCCCGGCUGGAGGGGAGGGAGUCACGAUGUCUGGUAGCCGCCAGGCCGGGUCGGGCUCCGCUGGGACAAGCCCCGGGUCCUCGGCGGCCUCCUCGGUGACUUCCGCCUCCUCGUCUUUAUCCUCUUCCCCGUCGCCGCCUUCCGUGGCGGUUUCGGCGGCAGCGCUGGUGUCCGGCGGGGUGGCCCAGGCCGCCGGCUCGGGCGGCCUCGGGGGCCCGGUGCGGCCUGUGUUGGUGGCGCCCGCCGUAUCGGGUAGCGGCGGCGGGGCGGUGUCCACGGGCCUGUCCCGGCACAGCUGCGCGGCCAGGCCCAGCGCCGGCGUAGGAGGCAGCAGCUCCAGCCUAGGCAGCGGCAGCAGGAAGCGACCUCUCCUCGCCCCCCUCUGCAACGGGCUCAUCAACUCCUACGAGGACAAAAGCAACGACUUCGUAUGCCCCAUCUGCUUUGAUAUGAUUGAAGAAGCAUACAUGACAAAAUGUGGCCACAGCUUUUGCUACAAGUGUAUUCAUCAGAGUUUGGAGGACAAUAAUAGAUGUCCCAAGUGUAACUAUGUUGUGGACAAUAUUGACCAUCUGUAUCCUAAUUUCUUGGUGAAUGAACUCAUUCUUAAACAGAAGCAAAGAUUUGAGGAAAAGAGGUUCAAAUUGGACCACUCAGUGAGUAGCACCAAUGGCCACAGGUGGCAGAUAUUUCAAGAUUGGUUGGGAACUGACCAAGAUAACCUUGAUUUGGCCAAUGUCAAUCUUAUGUUGGAGUUACUAGUGCAGAAGAAGAAACAACUGGAAGCAGAAUCACAUGCAGCCCAACUACAGAUUCUUAUGGAAUUCCUCAAGGUUGCAAGAAGAAAUAAGAGAGAGCAACUGGAACAGAUCCAGAAGGAGCUAAGUGUUUUGGAAGAGGAUAUUAAGAGAGUGGAAGAAAUGAGUGGCUUAUACUCUCCUGUCAGUGAGGAUAGCACAGUGCCUCAAUUUGAAGCUCCUUCUCCAUCACACAGCCUUGAAUUCAGUUCUGAUAUGCACAGGAUCUUUGUCAAUGGAAUACUUAUUAUUAGUAUUAUUGAUUCCACAGAAUACAGCCAACCUCCAGGUUUCAGUGGCAGUUCUCAGACAAAGAAACAGCCUUGGUAUAAUAGCACGUUAGCAUCAAGACGAAAACGACUUACUGCUCAUUUUGAAGACUUGGAGCAGUGUUACUUUUCUACAAGGAUGUCUCGUAUCUCAGAUGACAGUCGAACUGCAAGCCAGUUGGAUGAAUUUCAGGAAUGCUUGUCCAAGUUUACUCGAUAUAAUUCAGUACGACCUUUAGCCACAUUGUCAUAUGCUAGUGAUCUCUAUAAUGGUUCCAGUAUAGUCUCUAGUAUUGAAUUUGACCGGGAUUGUGACUAUUUUGCGAUUGCUGGAGUUACAAAGAAGAUUAAAGUCUAUGAAUAUGACACUGUCAUCCAGGAUGCAGUGGAUAUUCAUUACCCUGAGAAUGAAAUGACCUGCAAUUCGAAAAUCAGCUGUAUCAGUUGGAGUAGUUACCAUAAGAACCUGUUAGCUAGCAGUGAUUAUGAAGGCACUGUUAUUUUAUGGGAUGGAUUCACAGGACAGAGGUCAAAGGUCUAUCAGGAGCAUGAGAAGAGGUGUUGGAGUGUUGACUUUAAUUUGAUGGAUCCUAAACUCUUGGCUUCAGGUUCUGAUGAUGCAAAAGUGAAGCUGUGGUCUACCAAUCUAGACAACUCAGUGGCAAGCAUUGAGGCAAAGGCUAAUGUGUGCUGUGUUAAAUUCAGCCCCUCUUCCAGAUACCAUUUGGCUUUCGGCUGUGCAGAUCACUGUGUCCACUACUAUGAUCUUCGUAACACUAAACAGCCAAUCAUGGUAUUCAAAGGACACCGUAAAGCAGUCUCUUAUGCAAAGUUUGUGAGUGGUGAGGAAAUUGUCUCUGCCUCAACAGACAGUCAGCUAAAACUGUGGAAUGUAGGGAAACCAUACUGCCUACGUUCCUUCAAGGGUCAUAUCAAUGAAAAAAACUUUGUAGGCCUGGCUUCCAAUGGAGAUUAUAUAGCUUGUGGAAGUGAAAAUAACUCUCUCUACCUGUACUAUAAAGGACUUUCUAAGACUUUGCUAACUUUUAAGUUUGAUACAGUCAAAAGUGUUCUCGACAAAGACCGAAAAGAAGAUGAUACAAAUGAAUUUGUUAGUGCUGUGUGCUGGAGGGCACUACCAGAUGGGUAUCCUAGAAUUGCAUGGGAGAAGCAAAGAUCCCAUCUCUGUCACAUCCAAUCUUGGAGCCACCGGUGGAAAUUUAGAAGUGCCAAAGUGUUUCCAACAGUCGCUGCCGCAAACCUAUUCUUUCUUUACAGGAGUGAUUAGGUACUGUCUCAAACCCUCCUGAGUGCCACAUCAGGAGGCUCUCUAUGGUCUGUUGGUCACUUUGGAAGAUGUAGAGACUAAAUCCAAGGGAGACAUUAGAUAAUAAGCCAGGGUUCUCAUCAGUCUCCUCAGUAGCAAAAGCAAAGGCUAGAACAUUCUGGUAGUGCUCAUUAUUAAUUGGAACAUUACAGCUGGAGUCAAAGAUCUGCCUCCUGAAAGGUACUGUGUUCUGAUGUUUACAGCCAAAUUCCAUUAAACAUUGACUGAUUUAUUACAAUGGAUACAACUCAGAAAUAGCUCAUGGGAAGAGAUGCAUAGGGCAAGGUAUUGGAGAGUGGCGGGUGGAGUACACAGAAUAGGUCUGUGCUGGUGACUCUUGGAAACACUUUGGCAUUUUCUUCCCAGAUGGGUACCCUCCUAGUACCUCAAUGUUUUCACCAACCUGGAGGCCCUGGAACCUCCAUUUUCAACAAACUCCCUUUGGGAUUUAUAUAUAAUAAAAUGCUAUAAAAUAUCAGUUUUUGAGCUCUUUUCUGUUUGUAUAUUUGCUUAAUAAGAAUUUGCUAAAUGAAUAAAUUUUAUCUGAUUAAGUUUUCAAGGACCCAAAUGACCAAAAUAAGAACUUACUGUAAGACUCAAAAUAUAACAAAUGAGGUUAAUUUAAAUCAGGCAGUGAGUUUUUGGAGAAUAUGUUCUGUACAACAAAAAAAAAGUUACUACAAAAUACCCUUCCAACUUUGACAUAUUAACAUCCUUAUUUCCUUCUGGCUUUAUCAGUCUUUCUAAGUCAUUUAAGUCUAAAACCCCAGAAUCAUUAUUGUUGCAUCUCUUUAUUUUCCAUCUAAUUAUUCAUCAAAUAGCAGUAAUGCUUUCUUUGAAAUGUCUUCUAUAUAUCUUUGUUUUCGUUUCUGCUUUUCAUCUCCUCAUUUCUGUUCCUUCCCCUUCCCCUUCUCUCGAUUUACUUCUAACAGCUUUAUGUCCCUUUCAGUCGGCCUUUAUGCACUACCAAAUAUUCAUCUUUAUACAGAGAUAAUCAAUCAAACAUUGCUUGUUACCUUUAGUUGACCCAGGUCUUUCAGAAAAGUUUUUUUCAAAUUCAGCAUUUGCAUGUACCUCUAUCUGGUAUAUUUUGGCCAACACUAAAAAUAAGGGGAAAUUUUGAUAAAUAUAUUACCUGAACUUGUUAGUUAUUUAAUCUAUUUCACUUCAGAUAUCUGUAUCUAAUUUUAAAAUUAUAUUUACCCUUACUAUUAAAUAUGAUCCUUAAGAAAAUUAUAGGAAAAAGUACAAUAGAAAAAAAUACUCAAAGGUAACUCAGAUUUCAAAAUUUACUAGUAUUUAGAAAAUUAGCCUUUAUAAUAAGUAUAGAACAAUGUCGUUCCUAUAUCUACUUCUUAACUGCUCUAUUUCCUGAUCUCAUGUGUUUGCACUUAGACUAUCGUAUCUAAACUAUUACAUUCAAGAUUUUCAAUAAUCUAAUAUAAUGCUAUCCAUCUAACUUUAUUUCUGUUUUCUAACACAGUUCACCUACUUCAUUAAGAAAGUUUCUUCAUUGUCCCAUACUAUUCCCAUUCCGGCUUCUAAACUCGUAUUCAUGUUGUUCUUCAUAUUGCCUUAUCCUCUUAUUUCUGCUUAACUAAGUUCUCAUCAUUUUUUAGCCCAAUCACUGCUUCUCUUUCCCUCUUUUAACCAUUUUAUCUCCUUGGUUUCUGGUUUCUCACAGCUAUUGAUGAACCUAUAGAAUGCAGUCUACCAACUGAUGUUCACAUUCAUCUUGAAUUGUUUGUUAUGCUUCAUUAGUGUUGCCCCAGGUACAUUCCUUGCUUCAACUUGGAGAGCAAAAAAAUACAAACACCAGCAGCUACCAGAGUAAGAGCUACUUAGUUUUCUAGGAAAGAGGAGUUAAAGAUUGAGUGAGAAUAAAAUUUAAGUCUGCCUAACCCAGAGAGCCUACUUUUAUCAAUUUCAUAAGAUCAUAAAUAUACUGACUAGAAUAAUACACUAGUAUUAUUACUACUAGUACACUGUGAUACUGACAGUACUAAUAUGAUACUAAUAGUACUAUCAUUGCUUGAGAUAACUACCCUUUAACUGUAAAGAAAUUAAGGUUAUAUAGUAUUUUAGUAAAAGCAACUACCAUUCAUUUGUUUAGUGCCUAUAGUGUGCCAGUUACUCUUUGGUUACAUGCUGUAAGGGAGAAAAGAUUUUUCUCACCUGUUGGCUUGAUUCAUGACGGAGACCUCUGUAAGUUUUACAUGACAUAGAAGUUUUACGUGACACAGAAGGCUUCAGAAAUGAAGACCCAAAGAAUGGGUAAACUUGUAUAUGUUUAUGCUUAGGUUUGAUGAAGAAAUGAAUAGUCUCAUGGAGAAGUAUGAUUGGAGGACAAAGGGGUAUGAUCUAAUGGUAAUAAACUGGGGGCAACUUAGCAAGACCUGUUUGUUGAGCUUCUUCUCUGUGUCUCUGUCUCCAGAGAUAAGGGCAUUCCUUUCCUCAGGUAAGGAUAGGCAACUCUGGAAUGAGAGUCUUAUGACCUGCUUCAGUGGAAGGGCAGAGAAUUCUUUUAUGACCUGCUUCAGAGGAGAAGUGUGGGAGAAGGUCUUCCUGCUUCUGCUGUUUUUUCAAAUACCAAGGUGACUAUUUGGAGGUAGUGUGUUCUGGUCCCUAACAAUGCUCUACUGUGUUUUCCUUGAAUCUUCAUACAGAUUCUACCUAAGAGUAUCUGCUUUAUAUUUGGAGAAAUUGAAUGUCUAAAAGGAUUAAGCAGAACCAAAAUUCAGAUCCAGGUUUCCAUGCCUUGAAUGUAUUGCUUUUUCUGUUAACAUGGUAUUCCCCAAAUAGUACUGAAUUCUAGAAUCAGCUUUACCAGAGUAGUCUGGAGGAAAUUUGCGAAUAGCUCUCUUAAAUAUGCACGGUUCUAUGCUCAGAGGAGCUCUUCUCAGUAUUAAUCAGCAAUCCAGUCAUUUUUUUCCCCUCAUACUUGUCAUUGUAAGCACAUUUUUCUCAAGCUUUACUCAGAAGAUCAUCCAGAGAUAUUAACUGUUAACAUGUGCUGCAAGUUGAAAGUGUUUAGAGAGAAUAUUUGAGUGCAGUGUGACAAGGAUAAUCAAGUUGUUUAGGGCCAGUUGGCGAGAAGACUUUGGAAAGCAUUGAGAAAGGAAUGAUGAAUGUAUGUGUUGUUUUGUAUCUAAAUCCUUCUUCCCUUGUGUAUGUUCUUCACAGCCUUUUCUCCCUGAAUAAGGAUCACUUUGACUUUGUAUGCUAAGUGUGCCUUCUUAAUGGUUCUUUUCCUGUUAUCUGAAUCCUGAAGUAUAUUUAAAUGAGAAUUUGAUGCAGUUAGUUAAUUGGAAUAUAAAAGACUGGUUAACAAAAGUCUUCUUAAUAAUGAAGCACACCAGAAAUGGAAGCUGCUGGAACCAGCCAUGUGGACAAAUGAAAAAAUGCCUUUUGUCUACAGAUUGCAGCGAUCCUACAUAAAUAUAUGGAGGUCUCUGUCUGGCUUAGGACAGCUGGCUAAGUCUGAUCGUUCCCCUCCGUACAGCCUUUAAAACUGCCACUCUAAAUACUUGGUUUCCUUGCCAUUUUAUUCAGUAUCUGCUGGUUAUGAGUACUGUAUUAUUUUUUAAAUGGGCAACCAAGUAAAGUUACCUCUGUAUCCGUCUGAACUGGUUUUUGAGGUAUCUUACGAGUUUUGAAAAUAGGUGUUAUUUGCUUAUUUAAGGAACCUACAACCAGGAAGUAGAAUGAAUGUGGAAAUAUUAUUCUUCUCUUGCCGAGCAUGGUGGCUCACACCUGUAAUCCCAGCACUUUGGGAGGUUGAGGCAGAUGGAUCACUGAAUGUCAGGAGUUCAAGACCAGCCUGGCACCAACAUAGUGAAAUCCUGUCUCUACUGAAAACACAAAAAUUAGCCAGGUGUGUUGGCAGGCGCCUGUAAUCCCAGCUACUUGAGAGGCUGAGACAGGAGAAUCACAUGAACCUGGGAGGCGAAGGUUGCAGUGAGCUGCGAUUGUGCCAUUGCACUCUAGGCUAGGUGACGGUGCGAGACUCCAUCUCAAAAAAAAAAGAAAAAAGAAAUAUUAUUCUUCUAAGGGGCCACAUUGGCUUAACGAAUUCAGGGUUACCAGUGAAGGUCAAUACUUUAGAUAUGAAGGAGCUAAUCAGAGAUAGCUUCCGUGAAGAUUUUCUCAUUAAGAAAGUGAUUUCUCCAAAAUCCAGUUUAUGUAAUUUUUUAAGGCUGUAACCAAAGUUCAGAAAUAACCAUUUGCAGAGGAAAGCUGCUGCUAAGUAUUAACCUUCUUAGUACUGAAUUCAAAAUCUUGGUUUUUCCUGUUGUGUGUUUUGCUGUUAAGUUGUGGGGAGAGGUUGCUCCCACCUACCUCCCCUAACUUCUACAACUUACAGCAGCCACAGCUGGGUUUGUUUGUUUGUUUGUUUGUUUGUUUGUUUGUUUUUUGAGACUGAGUCUCACUGUGUCACCCAGGUUGGAGUGCAGUGGCAUAAUCUCAGCUCACUGCAACCCCUGCCUCCUGGGUUCAAGCAAUUCUCAUGCCUCAGCCUCCUGAGUAGCUGGAAUUACAGGGGACCACCAUGCCUGGCUAAUUUUUGUAUUUUUAGUAGAGAUGAGCUUUCAACGGCGCGGUGGCUCACGCCAGUAGUCCCAUCACUUUGGGAGGCUGAGGCGGGUGGAUCACCUGAGGUCAGGAGUUUAAUACCAGCCUGGGUUUAUUUAUAACUAAUUGUAUGAGGAUCCUUGUUUGUGGUUCUGAAAUCCCAUAUUUCUUACCCUGAGCAGUUUUUGCAUUAGACAGUUGUCAAAUGAGUAGCCAUACUUUUCUAGGCCCUUUAGAAAUCCACUGUUCUGUUCAUUCUAAUGAACGAUUUUAAGAUUUUGUAAGGAAGGAUACUAGUGGAGAAGAAAGAAGAGAUUUGGGAUUAACUGAUUUUGAAAGUGUUCCUUUGUGAUGAAGAAAUCCCAAUUCCCCAGAUCUCAAAUUGGGAUUUUGUGUAUGGGGGGUGGAAGAUUGGAAGGAGAGUGGGAAUUUGGCCUGUCAAUGCCAUGUAUGUUGACUUUGGAACACUCUUUACCACUUUGGUUCUGUGGCCAAGCCUUUUCCUCUGUUGAUAUUACUUGAAAUAAUACUUAUAGGGAGAUAUAUAAAAGACCAAAUUUUCCAUGUAACAAGGCUUUUAGGAGCCUAGGUUUAUGACAUUUGAAAUGUAAUGUAUAUUUAUAAUGUAUGAGAACUGAGGCUCUCUUGUACAUAGUCAGUGACCACCCAAGACACCUUUCUUCUUUCUUCCAUUUUGCUUUAAUAAAUUCAGGAUGAAGCCCAGACAUGUGAUAAGCUUACUGGGUCAAUAUGAUACAGAUCAGCAUUGGUAUAUUUCUCAGUUUUCACAAGUUGAUUCCUGGCUUUGCUCUUUCUUAGCUGUGUGUAUGAAUUUGGACAAGUUAUUAAGUCUAAGACUAUGUUUACUCUUUGUAAAUUGAUGAUAAAAAUAGUACCUUCCUCAUUGGGUUGCCAUGCAGAUUAAGUGAAGUAAUCCAUAUAAAAUUCUUAACUAAGUCACUGACCUAUAGUGCUCAAUAAAUAUGUGAUAAUGAAACAGGUUUUUAAGUGUUUGUGUGUGUGUGUGUGUGUGUGUGUGUGUGUGUGUAUUGCAAACACAAUUCAGACAGCUAAUUCACUCAACCCCCUUGGAUUUUUUAUAGAAUGCAGGGAAGGCUAACUAACAUUUUAGUUUAAAGACCAAGACCUUUUAUUGAUAGAUUGUAGUUUUGUGUUCAUUCUUUCUUAGACAUAUUUAUAUAUAUUUUUACCAAGUCAACUCUGAAAGACCACAUACUGAAAGAAAAGUCAGGGACAAAAAGAAACUAUUAGGCUUACAAAUGGCAUUUAAAAACCUUUGAAGAUGAUAUUGGAACCUAUGUUUGAAUGUCUUUGUAUGGACUCUCACUUGGUUUCAAAAUGCAGCGUAGAUUUAUGUCUAGGAUAAAGUAAAGAAACACUCCGGUCAAAUAAGGGGAUUCUUAUGAUGAAUCAAACCCAGAUAAGUGGCUGGGUGCGGUGGCUCACGCUUGUAAUCCCAACACUUUAGGAGGCUGAGGCGGGUGGGUCACGAGGUCAGGAGUUCGAGACCAGCCUGACCAACAUGAUGAAACCCCGUCUCCAAAUACAAAAAUUAGCUGGGUUUGGUGGCACGCACAUGUAAUCCCAGCUACUCAGGAGGCUGAAGCAGGAGGAUCACUUGAACCCGGGAAGCGGAGGUUGCAGUGAGCCGAGACUGCACCACUGCAGUCCAGCCUGAGCGACAGAGCGAGACUCCAUCUCAAAAACAAACAAACAAACAAAAACAAAACAAAAAAAAAACCCAGAUAAGUGAAAUGAAUUUCUCUGAGCUCCAAAAACAAAAGAAAUUUGAAUUUUAAAAGAUGUACUAGAAAGUGCUUUAAAUAAAAGAAUGAUUCUGCGUGUCAGGAAAUCAACAGUGGCCCAAUAGGAUGAAGUAACAAAAUGUCAGCACGAGUGAUGAAAUUGGACAAUUGAAUAGUAUCACUUAACAAGGCGUUGAACAAAGAAAAAUUUAAGAAUCCCUAUAUCUUAUAUCUGUAUUUCUUCUCAAGGGCAAGGGAGAGGAUGUUCAUAAGGCAACUAUAGAUCAUGCAUCAAAAGAAGGGCAAAUUUAUUUGAAAUUGUUCUGUGGCUGUAGGAUCCUGAGUGAAAAUCAGAUUUGACUAUACACAGAGUCCAUGACCUCCUACAUGAGGAGAGAAGCUAUUUUAGUUUUCAGGAUGCAAUUGCAGUACAAAUAGUAACAGCCCACCCUGAAGACAGAAAAAAAAAAUGGAGCAAAAGCCCAUUCUUUUAUGUUUAUAAUCUUGGUAUGAAAAAGAGCUUAAGGCAGGUAUGGUCUUUUAUUUUCAGUGACAUGAAAUCAUCUUUGUAUGAGUGCAAAUUAACACUCUCUUUUCUGGCAAUGAGAAAACAAGACAUUUGUGUUCAUAAAGAGAAUGCCUUUGUCCAAAUAAGACAAGAGGCUCUUAUGGAGAGAAUAUUAAGGAAUUAACAGAUAUAGUAUAGAUUGUGAGUUUUUUUGUGUGAAGCCUAGUUACCUCAAAUUUUUAUUCUUUAUAUUUACUUAAGGAAGGAUAUUUAAAUUCAGCCAUGUUUCUCACUGUUCUGUGCCCUCCAGGGAGCUGUAUUUGCAGAUACUGUAUGUUGUUCAUAGUGAUUUACCAUUUCCAUUUAAUCAAAUGCUUGUUAAAGGACUUAAAUGGACAUACAAUUUAAACUUAGUGGGCACACUUUAAGAAGAAAAUUCAGUGAUUAUAGGACAAAUUGUUUAAGGCAGAACUGCUUAUAACUUUGCUAGCCAUCUCAGCUGCAGUUUCUGCUUUUAGAGGACAAAUGUAAAUAGUAUUUCAGUGUACUUUACAUUUUCUGUGUCACUAAUAGUGUUCUACCACUUGAAAGGGGAACUAAAAUUAAAAAUCAUCUUCUGGGCUUUUUUUCCCCAGUAAAAUUUUCAAGGAACUUACCUUCCUUUGUCAUGAAGUUGUUUUAGGGGAGAAAACAUUUCUGAUUUUUGUUGGCUUUUUUUUGUUUUUGUUUUGUUUUUAGAUCCUUAUUUAGCAAGGUUAUGCUUUUAAACAUCUAAGGGUAGAGGGUGGGAUAUGUGUCAUUUAUUACCUUCUGUCUUGGGGUAAUGUUCUGAUUGAGAGUGCUGGAGCCAAGUUGCCAGGUUUGCCUCCUAUCACCAUUAAGUAUUAGCUGUAAGACUUUGGGAAAGUUAUUUAACCUUUCUGUGCCUCAGUUUCCUCUUCUGUGAAAUUAGAUUAAUAGUAUCUUGCAUGUAAUAUUCUGAAAUAAAAUUAGAAAAUACAUGGAAAGUACUAAGAAAAUAGUUGGCACAAGAUAAAUGAUCAAUCAGUAAAUGUUGCUGUCAUCUUUAACAUUUUAUAUACGAAUCCACAUAACUGGACAACUGUACUUGUUUUUAGUUCAUCAAAUAUUGUGCAAUAUGAAAAUAUAUUCUCUGCAUUUAAGUGAUUUACAACCUAGUAAAUAGAAAUAUUCAUAAAUAACUAUAGUAUGAACCCAAAUGAAAGAAAUCUUUAUAAGAUCAUUACCCCUGAAAUUAUUGACCCUAGAGGGAAGACGUUACUUCUAACUUGGAGAAUGAUGGAAUACUUUAUGAAGAUAGGGGCUUUUGAGCUGGGCUUCAUAAAGAUAUAAAGGGUUUCAGAAGUCUAAAGACAAAGGGAAAGGAAGGUACCUGGACAAAAGACCAUAAACAAACACAUCUAUUAAGUACCAACCAGGCAGUAUACUAAGUGCUAUCUUAAUUUAAAAUCAUCAUCAUCAAUCUUUUAAGGCAUAUAUGCUUGAGUUCCUUUAAAAGUGAAAUUGACGCUCAGAUUUGCCCAAGAUUACACAGCUAAAUAAGGGAUACAGUUGGAAUUAGAACCCAGGUCGGGCUGGCUGUAAAACGUACACCCUUUCUGCUAUACUGCAGAAAGCUAGAGAACAGUGUAAACAAAGGCGCAGAUGAGGGAAAGUGCAAUAGAUGUUUAAGAAACUUCUAAUAAAGUGUCUAAGUAGGAUGGUGGAGUAGGGACUUUAUUGAGAGAUGAGGCCAGAGAGUGUGCUAGAUAUUAUAGUCUUGAAUGCCAUACUGAGAGAAAAAAAAAAAGUUUAGACCUUCUUCUGUAGGCAUUAAAUGCCUAAAGCCCACUGUGAAGAUAAUCCCAUGAGAGUAUUAUCAUAGCAGUGGGUAUAGUGCAUUGUAAUGAGAGAUUAAAAGUAGAGAGUCUACUCAGGUAGGUUAUUAAAUAAUUUAAUUAUUCAGGGUUUUUUUUUUCUGUGUUCAGUUUCCUUCUGGGGAAUAAGAAUAACAGAAAACACCCACAUGUAACAUUCAUGUUUUUCAAGAUGUUAAGUUUGCCCUCACAUAUUAAAAAAAAUGUUUAUUUGACGAUGUUUCAUUAUAUUCACUUCAAACAAUAAAUCUUGAACUAUGUUUGCGGAUAUAAUCAUUAACUUCUACCUUCUAGUACACAACUUAAUUUUUUUUCUGCUUUUCCAAGAAUUCACUUAUUUAACUUAACACAUGUGAAUUGAAGAGUUUUGUUAAGAGAUAGGAUUAAAGGAGAUGACUCUAGGUGCCCAGGGAGGGGGAGGUGCGGUGAGAGAUGGCUGAAGGAAUAGAACACUGGUGGGAAGCAAAGUUCUUUUCUACCCUCUUAGGUUCUCUGGCUAGGUCUGUGAAAUAAACUGACAACUGAUGGAUUAACAGAAAAGGCAUACAAAUUUAUUUGAUAUUCAAAGUUUUACAUGAAUCAGCUGCCAGGGGUGGGUUGGAAUAGUGGGGGAUAUCUCGUAGAAAGAAAACCCCCAAUGAAAAGGCUCGGUUUGGAGGUUUUUAUACCAUUUAGACAAGAAGACAAAUUUAAAGGGAAGCGACAAGACAAAGGAAAGGGACUUUGAGCUUCUAGGAGUGAUGAACAAUAGGAAGGCAAAUAUUAAUAUAUAAGAAACUAAUGGUAGAUAAGGGCUAGUUAGUGAGGUUUGUGCAGAUUUUUUCUCAGUACCAUCUCAUCUUUGGUAAUAAUAAUAAGGUUGUUAUCCCUUUCCUGGUACAGGAAGUAACUGGGGUACAGGGAAUUCCUCUCUUUCACAAGAGGAAUUUAUUGUCUGUUUUCAGGCAGAUAGAAGGAGAGCAGAAAGCUCUCCUCAGUUGCUUUCAGCUCAAAAUAAUCUUUCCACCAGAGUAGCAUAUUUUGGGAUGGCAUAUUCUGAUCUACAACACCAAAGAAAAACUGCUCCUAUCUAUUUUUUGCAUAAAGGCAGUCACUGACUUUUGUUAUCCAUAAAUAAAAUUCACAGAUAAAUUAAUCUUACUUAUUUUCUAACCCUGGUAUGCUACAGUUUACAUGCUUACCCCACCUCAUAUUUUCAUCUCGUUAACUAAUACAUAAGCUGCUUUCUCCACACAAUUUGUCAUCAUUCCAAAACCAUUUUUUUUUUUCAAAUUUAUUCCAUGUGCAUGACCGUGUCCCUUUGCCUAACAUAUCCAUCUUUUCUCCUGUGAAAUUUCAAGUUUUAUUCUUCCAUUGUUCCAUUUGUGACCUAAUCUGUGAAGCCUUUCUUAUCUUUUCCAAGUAAAGGAUCACUCUCUUCUUACUUCUUCAGUUGCCCCUUUGAGCUCUAUAAUAUAUUCUUUUUUUUUUUUUUUUUUUUUUGAGACAGGGUCUCACUCUGUUACCCAGGCUGGAAUGCAGUGGCCCAAUUCAGGCCCAUUGCAGCCUUGACCUCCCAGGCUCAGGUGAUCCUCCCGCCUCAGCCUCCCAAAGUGCUGGGAUUACAGGCAUGAGCCACCACACCCAGCCUAUUUCUUUCUGUUAAAAGUCCAUUUCCCCUGUUGGCCUAUGGUCUUAAGAUCAGACAUCAUGUCUUAUUCUCCUUUGAAAUUCCAGGACCCAGCACAAUUAUCUGGCAUGUGAUAUCUACCCUAAUGGACGGAUAAUGAUGGAUGAAUAAAGUGGCAUGAAAUUAAUAAACUUCAUGCCAAAGUCACUACUGUAUAAUGAAACGACUGUGAUGAUUGAAAGUUAUUCUCUCUGUGAAUCAAUUUGGGAGCGUUUCUUUAUGUCUUAGUCAGGGUUCUCCAAAGGGACAGAAGUAAUAGGACAUGUAUAGUUAGAUCUAUGACAGGGUUUUUAUUUGGGGUAUUAGCUCACAUGAUUACAGAGGGUGAGACAUACCAUGAUAUGCCAGGGAGGCCAGUAGCAUGGCAGAAUCUUAGGCUAAAGGCCUGAGAAUUUGAGGGCCCAUUGAUGCAAGUCCCAGAGUCCAAAAGCUGGAGAAUCUGGACUUCUGAUGGCCAAGGCCAGGAGAAGAGUGUCCCAGCUCCAGGAGAGAGGAAGCAAAUUCACCUUUCUGCUCCCUUUUUGUCUAUCCAGGCCCCCAGCUGAUUGGAUGGUGCCUAUCCACAUUGAGGGCUGAACUUCCCCACUCAGUCAACCGACUCACACACCAGUCUCUUCUGGAAACACCCUCACAGACUUACCCAGAAGUAGUGCUUUGCCAGUUCUCUAAGUAUCCCUUUAUCCAGUCAAGUUGAAACCUAAAAUUACCCAUCACACUGUUACCUUGGACAUCAGGAGUAGCUUUCUGGCGAAGCCUCUGUCAAAGCCAGUUUCUAAUGGCUAAGUUAGCCAGGGACUUAUAAAGGCCCUUUAUAAUGCAAACUUGACCAUUUGGUGGAGUUGCUUUUGAUGUUACCAGUACCAUCUAAUGUCCAAAUCCAAUAACAUAUUAUUACUAAACAGUCUUCAUUUCCUCAUGAUUUUUGACAAUUUUGACUUGCUUCUCUUUCUUAAACUCUUCUUUUAGCCUCCAUAAUAGUCUUCUGUUUUGCUUCCUGCCCCUUUGUUCAUUUUGGGCUCCUUUGCUUGCCUUCCUUGAACUGCUAAGCCAGAAGCAAUUUUCCCUCACUUAAAGAUCACUUAUAAGAUACAUACUUUAUGCCAGGCACUUAUGUAUGUGUCUGUUUGAUCAUAAAAAUGGUUCUGUUAGCUUAGUUUUAUUAGCAUUGUUUUAUAGUUAUGGAGACUGAGAUUCAGAGAGGUCAAGUAACUUGCCCAUAAUGAAAAGUCUAGAAGCGUUAGAGCUUUGAAUUGAAAUCUUUCAGACUCCAAAGACAUUUAAUCUACUCUGUCACUCUGUCUAUGUUUUGUCCACCUGUUAAUUUGAUUUUAGGAAUACAGAUUGUCGUAUAUAAAUUCUGGUCCAUUUCCUCCUGAAAACCAGUUACUGGCAUUUCCAUGAAUAUAGAAAACUCUGUAAAAUUGUUUUUUCUAUAAGAGAAGCCUACAGACCUCUCUUAGGUGAUGAAGAGGCUUAGAAUUGAAUAUCAAAUUUGGCUUGCCACUUAAAACAGAAUGGAGUCUCAAGUUGCAAGUAGGGUUGUUUGUUAAACCUGAAACACAAAACAAGAUAAAGGGAGGAUAUAACCACCAAAUAGAAAACUUUUGACUCUGUACAUUUUGAGAAAGCCCUGAAGAUGUAUUUGAUCUAUUAUACAAUUCAGGUUUACAUUAAUGAUGGUAAUUUACCUAGAAAGAUUUCACACCUGAUAAUAGUAGUUGACUCUCUAGGGAGAUGAGAGACACUCAGUUUUCCCCUACUCUUUUGUACUGUGUGAAUUUUUACCACAUGUGUAUAUUAUCUAUUCAAGUUAACCAAUAAACAUAUUUUUCUAAAUAAGAGAAAGGUAUCUAGGUAGUCCUUAAGGGAUCCAUUAUUUAUUAUCCCCAUUUUUAAUCCAACCAUCUUGCUAAACUCUCUUAUUAAUUUUAAUUAUUCAUUUCUACGUUCCUUGGAUUUUUUUAUGCACACAAUUAAUUCAUCCACAAAUAAUUAAAGUUUAGUGUCUGCUUUUCCAGUACUUAUACCUUUAUAUCUUUAUUCAUUUGCCGUAUUUUGAUGGCCAGAACAUCUAAUGUAAUGUUAAAUAAAAGUAAUGGUAUCUGGCAUCGUUGACUUGUUCCUCACCAAAGGGAAAGCUUUUAAAGAUGUUAUCAUUAAGUAUGUCUGCUGUAAGAGUUUUGUAGAUACAUACCCUUACAAAGAAGUUUCCUUCAGUUCUCAAUGUGCUGAGAGUUCUUACCAUAAAUGAAUGCUAAAGUAUAUUACUGCUUUUUUGUACCUAUUUAACAUGAUAUAAUAUUUUUCUUUCAAAUAUUGAUCUAGUAGGUGAAAUUUUUUUUUAACCUAAUAUUAAACCAACUUUACAUUCGCUGGAAUAAGCCCAACUUGGUCAAGAUUUAUUCUCCUUAUAUAUUGUUAAAAUCAACUUGCUACUAUUUUGUUUAGGAUUUUUUCAUUUGUCUUUAUGAAUAACAUUGGCCUAUAAUCUUUUCCUUUUUUGCAUUGUCCAUGUCAGGUUUUGAUUUCAUGGGUAUAUUAACUUCAUAAAGCAAAUUAAGGAGUUCUUUCCUCCUUUGAUGUGGAAAAAUUUGUGUAAUACGAAAUUAUUUCUUUCUUGAAUAUUGGCUGAACUCGUAGAUGAAGUCAUGUAAGCCUGAGGUAGAAAUAUUUUUGACUGUCGAUUUAUGAAUUUAAUACCUGUAGGAUGAUUCUUGCUUUCUAUUUCUUCUUGAUUAGUUGGGUAAGUUUUUAUAGGAAUUUUUCCACUUGGCUUAAAUAUUAAAAUUUAUUAACAUAAAGUCUUUUCAGUUUCUUUUUUCUAUAACAUUAUUUAUUCUCAUUCUGAGGGAAGUCAUCAAUUUAACGUAAUGCUUAACAUUUGGAGAAAUAAAUUUUAAAGAAGGGUUAUAUUCUGAUUUUGUUUAAUAGUUAUCUUCUGGUUAAUAAAAGGAGGAGAAAUGUAGGGUGGAAAUGCUUAUCAUAGUAAAUAGCAAGGUUUAUAUAUAAAACCAUCUAUAUUGAACAGGGAGAGAGGAAUGACAAAAAUAUUUACCUUUCUUUUUGAUAAUUCAGUGCCUUAUUUUGGGGGAAAUAUUUAGCUUCAUAGCUGAAAUGGCUUUGAUAUUAUACCUGAAUGGUUACAGAGAUCUCAUAAAUAUAGUAGUGAUAAGGGGUUUAUAUAUUAUGUUGGGAAAUCAGAAAAUAUUUAAAUCAUGAAUAAUGACUUUUAAUUGUUAAAGACCAAUAUUGAGUUUAAAGUUAACUUAUAAAAUACGUAUUUGUUCUUGUGUGUUUGUUCCCAGCUUUUUAAAAUUGAUAUUAUUGAAAUAUAAUUUACAUAAAUAUAAACUACAUACAUUUUAAGAGUAUUCAGUGAAUUUUUACAAGUGUAUACAUCAGUAUAACUACUACCUUAAUUCAGUUAUAACAACAUUUUCAUCACCCAAAAAGUUACCUUGUGUCACUUUGUAAUCAGUCCCCUCCCUUCUCCACUACAAGCUACUGCUAAUCCACUUUAUGUUAUCAUAAGUUAAGUUUUGCUUAUUCUAGGAUUUCAUAUAACAGGAAUGAUACAGUAUGUAAUUUUUUGCACCUGGCUCCUUUUAUUUAGCAUGAUACUUUGAAAUGCUUGUGUUAUUGCCUGUAUCUGUAGUUCCUUCUUAUUAGUAAUCCAUUUUAUAACUAUGCAACAAAUUUUGUAUCUAUUCACCAAUCUUUAAUAUUGCCCUUGUUUCCAGUUUUGAACUAUUUUUAAUAAAGCCGCUGUAAACAUUCAUAAAUAAGUGUUUAUGUGACUAUAUACCAUCAUUUCUUUUGGAUAAAUACCUAGGAGUGGCAUUAUGAGAUUGUAGAGUAGUUGUAAGUUUAGCCUUAUAAGAAACUGUCAAACCUUUUUCCAUAGUUGUUGUAUUACAUUCAUUGGUCACUUAACAAUGGGGAUACGUUUUGAGAAAUGCCAUUAGGUGAUUUGAUUUCAUCAUUGCACAAACAUCAUAGAGUGUACUUCCCAAACCUGGAUGGUAUAGCCUAGUACAUACCUUAGCUAUGUGGUAUAGCCUGUUGCUCCUAGGCUACAAAUUUGUACAGCAUGUUACUACACUGAAUAGUGUAGGCAGUUGUAACACAAUGGGAUUUGUGUAUCUAAACACAGAAAAGCUAUAGUAAAAAUACAAUAUAAAAGGUAAAAAAUGGUACACCUGCCUAGGGCAUUACCAUGAAUGGAGCUUGGUGGAGUAGAAGCUGCUCUCGGUGAGUCAGGGAGUGAGUGGUGAGUGAACGUGAAGACCCAGACAUUAUUGUACAUUACUGUAGACUUUAUCAACACUGUAUACCUAAGCUACACUAAUUUAUUUUAAAAUGUUUUCUUUCUUCAAUAAUAAAUUAACUAUAGUUUACUGUAACUUUUUACUUUAUAAUUUUAAUUUUUUUCACUUUUUGACUCUUUUGUAAUAACUUUUAGCUUAAAACACAAACACAUUGUACAGCUGUACAGAUUUUUCCUUAUUCUGUAAGCUUUCUUCCAUUUUUAAAUGUAUUUAUUUAUUUUUACUUUUUAAACAUUUUUUGUUAAGCUCAUCAACAUCACUGUCUUCUACAUCUUGUCCCAUCGGAAUGUCUUCAGGGACAAUAACACACAUAGAGCUGUCAUCUCCUAUGGUAACAAUGCUUUCUUCUGGAGUAUCUCCUGAAGGACCUGCCUGAGCCUAUUUUACAGUAACUUUUUUUGUUAAUAAGUAGAAGGAGUAUAAUCUAAAUUAAUGAUUAAGAAGUAUAGUACAAUAAUCUUAUUGGACCACCAUCAUAUAUGUGACCCAUCGUUGACCAAAAUGUCAUUGUGCAGUGCAUGACUAUAUUUUGCACUCCUGCCAGCAUCCUAAAAUCAUUCCAUUUGUUACAUAUUUUUGCCAACACUUGAUAUUGUCACUUUAAGAAAAAGAUUUAGUUGUUCUAGUAAGUGUGGAUGGUAUUUUAAAAUUUUUGAUGAAGUCCAAUUUAUCAGGGUUUUUUUUUUCCUUUAUUGUACAUGUUUUUUGCAUCCUAAAAAAUAGUUGCCAACCCAAAGAUUUUCUCUGAUUUUUUUUCUUGAAGUUUUAUUGUUUCAGCUUUUACAUGUAUGUCUUAGAUCUAUUUAGAAUUAAUUUUGGGAAUGGUAUGAUAGAAGGAUUGAAGUUUACUUUUUUCUGUAUAUACAGUUGUUUUAGCACACAUAUGGUUGUUUCACAUACCUGCAGUUGUUUCAACAGCAUUUGUAAAAAUUACUCUAUUUUUUUUUUAACUUGCCAAGUUGUUUUGAAAUUCAGUUGAUUAUGGAUGGAUCUGUUUCUGGAAUUUCUUUUCUGUGCCUUUGAUUUAUAUGUCUAUCCUAAUAAUACUACACUGUAUUGAUUCCUAAUGCUUUUAUUAACAGUAGAACUUCAAAUCAUGUUGUGUAAGUCCCUAGUUUUAUUUUUUCUUUUUCAAAAUUAUUUUAACUAUUAUAAUGUCUUUGCUUUUUCAUUUAAAUUUUUGAAUCACUUUGCCAGUUUCUACUAGAAAAGUUUGUAUGAUUUUAAUUGGAAUUGCAUUGAGCCUAUAGAUAAUGUAAGAAGAAUUGGCAUUGUGACACUAUUGAGUCUCUGGUCUAUGAACAUGGUAUAACUGUCAAUUUAUUUAGGUAUUCUUUAACAUCUCUAAGCAUUGUUUGGUAAUUUUUAGUAUGUAGGCCGUGUGUGUGUGUGUGUGUGUGUGUGUGUGUGUGUGGUUUGUCUCUAAAUGAUUCAUGCUUUUUAUGGUACUAUAAAUGGUAUUUUUUAAAUUCUAUUUGCUUAUCAUUUAUUGUUAGUUUAUGGAAGUGAACUGAUUUUGGUAUAAUUGACUUUGUGUCUGACAAUCUUGCUGAAGACAAUUUAUUUAUUCUAGUGGCUUAUUUUUAAGGUACAUUAGGAUUUUCCACAUAGGCCAUCAUCUCUUUUGCAAAUGAAGACAGUUUUCUUUUUUCAGAUCCAUAUGCUUUUUCCUUUUCUUGACUGUCGCACUGGGUUGUACCUCUAAUACAGUGUUGAAUACAAAUGGUGAGAGAAAGCAUGUUCACCUUGUUCCUAGUCUGAGAGAGAAAGGGUUCAGUAUUUCACCACUAAGUAUGAUGUUAGUUGUAAGUUUUUCAUAGGUAUUCCUUAUCACCUUGAAGAAGUUCCUUUCUAUUCUUAGUUUGCUGAAGGGAUGAUGAAUGCUCUCAAGUGCAUUUUCUGUGUUGUGAUUACAUUACUUUUUCUUUUUUUUGUUUUGAGGCAGGGUCUCACUCCUGUCACCCAGGCGAGAGUACAGUGACACAAUCACAGCUCACUACAGCCUUCCCAGGCUCAGGUGAUUCUCCCACCUCAACCUUCUGGGUAGCUGGGACUACAGGUGCAUGCCACCACACCCAUCUAAUUUUUUGUGUUUUUGAUAGAGAGGGUUUCGCCAUAUUGCCCAGGCUGGUCUCACACUCCUGGACUCAAGCAAUCCACCUGCCUUAGCUUCCCAGAGUGCUAUCACAGGCAUGAGCCACCCUACCUGGCCUUUUCUAUUCUCUUUACAUAGUGAAUUAUAUAUAUAUAUUUUUUAAUGUUGAAAACCAAUUUUAAUAUCUGGAUGAAUUCCAUUUAGACAUGAUGCAUUAUUCUUUUUGUAUAUGACUGAAUUAUCUUUACUUGUAUUUUGUUAAGGUUUUUUACAUCUGUUUAUAAAAGUAGUUGGUAAUUUUAUUUGUUUUUGUAAUGUCUUUCUCUGGUUUUGUUUGAUUUACAAGCUGAGUUUGGAAAUGUUCCUUAGUCUUCAUUUUUAACAACUUUUUCUUUCUUCUGUCAUAAUUGGGAAUUUGUAUCUUUCAUAGAAUUUGUUCAUUUCAUUACCUGUCAGUUUUAUUGACAUACAAUUGUUCAUGUUUAUUUUCUAAUUAUUCUUUUAAUAUCUAUAGAAUAUCUAGUGAUAUCCCAUAAUUUAUUACUGAUAUUGUUAACUUACAUUUUCUUUUUGUUAAGGCGUAUCAAUUUUAUUGAUUUUUUUCAAUGAAUUAACUUUUCAUUUCAAUACUUUUUUACCUUUUUCUGGUUUUAUUUUGAUUUCUGCUCUUCAUGACUGUCAUUCUUGUACUUACGUCAUGUGUAACUUGCUCUUUUCCUAGCUUCUUAAGGUGCAAGUUACUAUAUCAUUAAUGUUCAACCUUCCUGCUUUACUAAUAAGUAUUGGAAGCUAUAACUUUCUAGGCAUUGUUUUAGGUGCAUUACACAAAUUUUGAUAUGUUGCAUUUUUAUUAUCUUUUAGUUCAAAAUGGUUUCUCAUUUCCAUCCCUGGGUUAUUUGGGAGUAUAUUUUUAAAUUUGCAAAUACUUGUGGAUUUUUCCAGAUUUCUUUUUGUUAUUCUUUUCUACUUUAGUUCUGUUUCUUCAGAGAACAUACUUGUAUGAUUUUAGCCCUUUAAAUUUACUGUGAUUUGUUUUAUGGUCUGACACAUCUUUGUUGGGGACUAGUACGCAUGCAUUUGAAAAGAAUGUGUAUUCUGUCAUUUAAAUAAAACUUUCUGUAAAUGUCA